ACUCUACCCCGCGCCGUCUCACGGCCCCGGCCCUAGCUUCACCCCGACUACCCGGCGUGCGCGUCCUCCUGCCGGCCUGCAGGCCCGGGGCCUCCGCCUGCUUCCCCACAGCUGCUCCUUGCGGCCCCGCUUGCGUUCACGCUGUCGCCCGGGCCGGCGCGGCCGCGGGCAACCGCUCCCCCUCCCACACCUACCCCGCCCCCUCCCCGCCUUUUCCGCCCUCCGGUCCCCCUCCCUCGGCCCGCUGCUGCUGCUCCAGAUGAGGUGAUGGCAACGGCCAACUUCGGCAAGAUCCAGAUCGGGAUUUACGUGGAGAUCAAGCGCAGCGAUGGUAAAUACGAGUUCACAGUAUACCAGCAAAAGUAGGAUUUACAUAUUAUUUUGAAGAUUCUGGGUGCACAGCAACACCUGUCCCUGGUAUACACCCAAGGGAGAGGAAAUCACCACCUUGUGAAGAUAUCUGCACUCUCGCGUUCAUUGCAGCAUUAUUCACAGUAGCCAAGAUAGGGAAGCAACCUAAAUGUCCAUCGAUGGGCCGAAUACAUCAAGCAAUGGUAACAUCUUUAAAUGAAGAUAAUGAAAGUGUAACUGUUGAAUGGAUAGAAAAUGGAGAUACAAAAGGCAAAGAGAUUGACCUGGAGAGCAUCUUUUCACUUAACCCUGACCUUGUUCCUGAUGAAGAAAUUGAACCCAGUCCAGAAACACCUCCACCUCCAGCAUCCUCAGCCAAAGUAAACAAAAUUGUAAAGAAUCGACGGACUGUAGCUUCUAUUAAGAAUGACCCUCCUUCAAGAGAUAAUAGAGUGGUUGGUUCAGCACGUGCACGGCCCAGUCAAUUUCCUGAACAGUCUUCCUCUGCACAACAGAAUGGUAGUGUUUCAGAUAUAUCUCCAGUUCAAGCUGCAAAAAAGGAAUUUGGACCCCCUUCACGUAGAAAAUCUAAUUGUGUGAAAGAAGUAGAAAAACUGCAAGAAAAACGAGAGAAAAGGAGAUUGCAACAGCAAGAACUUAGAGAAAAAAGAGCCCAGGACGUUGAUGCUACAAACCCAAAUUAUGAAAUUAUGUGUAUGAUCAGAGACUUUAGAGGAAGUUUGGAUUAUAGACCAUUAACAACAGCAGAUCCUAUUGAUGAACAUAGGAUAUGUGUGUGUGUAAGAAAACGACCACUCAAUAAAAAAGAAACUCAAAUGAAAGAUCUUGAUGUAAUCACAAUUCCUAGUAAAGAUGUUGUGAUGGUACAUGAACCAAAACAAAAAGUAGAUUUAACAAGGUACCUAGAAAACCAAACAUUUCGUUUUGAUUAUGCCUUUGAUGACUCAGCUCCUAAUGAAAUGGUUUACAGGUUUACUGCUAGACCACUAGUGGAAACUAUAUUUGAAAGGGGAAUGGCUACAUGCUUUGCUUAUGGGCAGACUGGAAGUGGAAAAACUCAUACUAUGGGUGGUGACUUUUCAGGAAAGAACCAAGAUUGUUCUAAAGGAAUUUAUGCAUUAGCAGCUCGAGAUGUCUUUUUAAUGCUAAAGAAGCCAAACUAUAAGAAGCUAGAACUUCAAGUAUAUGCAACCUUCUUUGAAAUUUAUAGUGGAAAGGUGUUUGACUUGCUAAACAGGAAAACAAAAUUAAGAGUUCUAGAAGAUGGAAAACAGCAGGUUCAAGUGGUGGGAUUACAGGAACGGGAGGUCAAAUGUGUUGAAGAUGUACUGAAACUCAUUGACAUAGGCAACAGUUGCAGAACAUCCGGUCAAACAUCUGCAAAUGCACAUUCAUCUCGGAGCCAUGCAGUGUUUCAGAUUAUUCUUAGAAGGAAAGGAAAACUACAUGGCAAAUUUUCUCUCAUUGAUUUGGCUGGAAAUGAAAGAGGAGCUGAUACUUCCAGUGCGGACAGGCAAACUAGGCUUGAAGGUGCUGAAAUUAAUAAAAGCCUUUUAGCACUCAAGGAGUGCAUCAGAGCCUUAGGUAGAAAUAAACCUCAUACUCCUUUCCGUGCAAGUAAACUCACUCAGGUGUUAAGAGAUUCUUUCAUAGGUGAAAACUCUCGUACCUGCAUGAUUGCCACAAUCUCUCCAGGAAUGGCAUCCUGUGAAAAUACUCUUAAUACAUUAAGAUAUGCAAAUAGGGUCAAAGAAUUGACUGUAGAUCCAACUGCUGCUGGUGAUGUUCGUCCAAUAAUGCACCAUCCACCAAACCAGAUUGAUGACUUAGAGACACAGUGGGGUGUGGGGAGUUCCCCUCAGAGAGAUGAUCUAAAACUUCUUUGUGAACAAAAUGAAGAAGAAGUCUCUCCACAGUUGUUUACUUUCCACGAAGCUGUUUCACAAAUGGUAGAAAUGGAAGAACAAGUUGUAGAAGAUCACAGGGCAGUGUUCCAGGAAUCUAUUCGGUGGUUAGAAGAUGAAAAGGCCCUCUUAGAGAUGACUGAAGAAGUAGAUUAUGAUGUCGAUUCAUAUGCUACACAACUUGAAGCUAUUCUUGAGCAAAAAAUAGACAUUUUAACUGAACUGCGGGAUAAAGUGAAAUCUUUCCGUGCAGCUCUACAAGAGGAGGAACAAGCCAGCAAGCAAAUCAACCCGAAGAGACCCCGUGCCCUUUAAACCGGCAUUUGCUGCUAAAGGAUACCCAGAACCCUCACUACUGUAACAUACAACGGUUCAGCUGUAAGGGCCAUUUGAAAGUUUGGAAUUUUAAGUGUCUGUGGAAAAUGUUUUGUCCUUCACCUGAAUUACAUUUCAAUUUUGUGAAACACUCUUUUGUCUACAAAAUGCUUCUAGUCCAGGAGGCACAACCAAGAACUGGGAUUAAUGAAGCAUUUUGUUUCAUUUACACAAAUAGUGAUUUACUUUUGGAGAUCCUUGUCAGUUUUAUUUUCUAUUUGAUGAAGUAAGACUGUGGACUCAAUCCAGAGCCAGAUAGUAGGGGGAAGCCACAGCAUUUCCUUUUAACUCAGUUCAAUUUUUGUAGUGAGACUGAGCAGUUUUAAAUCCUUUGCGUGCAUGCAUACCUCAUCAGUGAUUGUACAUACCUUGCCCACUCCUAGAGACAGCUGUGCUCACCUUUUCCUGCUUUGUGCCUUGAUUAAGGCUACUGACCCUAAAUUUCUGAAGCACAGCCAAGAAAAAUUACAUUCCUUGUCAUUGUAAAUUACCUUUGUGUGUACAUUUUUACUGUAUUUGAGACAUUUUUUGUGUGUGACUAGUUAAUUUUGCAGGAUGUGCCAUAUCAUUGAACGGAACUAAAGUCUGUGACAGUGGAUAUAGCUGCUGGACCAUUCCAUCUUAUAUGUAAAGAAAUCUGGAAUUAUUAUUUUAAAACCAUAUAACAUGUGAUUAUAAUUUUUCUUAGCAUUUUCUUUGUAAAGAACUACAAUAUAAACUAGUUGGUGUAUAAUAAAAAGUAAUGAAAUUCUGAGAAGAGUUUUAUCUUAGGAAAAUACAUAUAUAUGCAGUGUGUGUGCCAGUGUGGUAUUAACAAGACUAAUAGUGCAGUUUGAUCCUUACCAAUAUCAUUACUUAAUUUGAAGUGUUCAUUAGCACCCCAAAAUAUACCUUUUCUAUGUACUGUUAAAAGAAAUUGGCUUCUGAUGCAUGAACAUUUACAUGUACAUUGAAAGUAGUCCAUAAUAGAAGUUAGUUUAAGCCAAGUGUAGACAGUACAUUACUCCCUUGAAAAAGAAUUAAGUUGAAAGAGUUGACUUUGCCUUAAAAGGCAGAUCUAACCCAAGCUCCAUCCAGUACCAAAUGUGAAACUUCAUUGUUGUUUGGUGAGAAUCGCCAAAUUCUCACUAAUACAUUGGUAUGGUGUAGGGCAUGCUACUUUUUAAACAGCAGCACUUAUUUUUACAGAUUGCUACUCCAAGGAAGAAAACUGGCCACUUUUCAUGUAAAUAUUUUGUUCAAAGAUUUGUAUAUCUCUCUAGGAGUUUUCCCUCAGUUCCCAGGAUGGGGUCCAGGAGUAGAUUAACAGCUAAAAAUCUCCCAAGGAUAUCUUGUUUUGAUUUAUUUACUCCAGGGAACUAUCAGCUCCUUCACAGGAGCCAAAGGGGAGCUAUGAAUAGAGGGUCACAUGAGCCAGAUUCUUUACUGUUCAUAAAACCCAGAGAGUAGUUGUGAAAGAUCCUAAUACAAUUGUGAAAAGCUCUGUAAACAUGAAAUCUAAAACAAAUGUAGAUUUUCACAAUAUGCUUAUUAAUAAAUGAAGUCUAUGGAAUAAGUUUUAGAGAUAAUUUACUUCAGUCACCUUUGUUUUGGAAAGGACUCAGGUUUUCUUGCAGCUGUAAGAUAUAUUCUAUUUGUGUUUAUUUCAAAGGGAAGAGGAAGGAUGGAGAACUGUUACAAUUGACCUUGCAAAGGAUAUUUAAAAAAAAGGUAGUUUUUGAGAUUAACCAACUUUCAAAGGGCAAUAAAGACAUGUGAAUUUGCUCAUUUUAAAGCACAACAGAUGAUUAGCUUCAAAUUUAUUAUUUGCAUUGGAUGGGUACUGUCUUUGGAAAGUCUCCUUAUAGACAAAUAUGCUGCCUUACACUAUGAUGGCUUCAUUCUGAUCAGGUAUUUUAAAAAUUAGUACCAGAAAAGAUACUGGAGGUAAUAUAAUACAGUCCUUCAGCUUUACAGAUAGUGAAAACUGAAGGCCAGAAAAGGAACUAAAACUCAGCAGUUCAUAGGGGUAGAGGGAAAUAACCUGAGAAAGCCGAGUUAAAUCUUAAAAUUUUUACUAUAAGGAUAGAGAUGAUACAAGUGAACUCUGCAAAAUAGUUUUGUGAAAUUAAACAAAAAAAUCUACUCUUAAUGUAUAUUAUUUCAUAUUUGUUUAACAAAAGCAGCUUGAUGCCUUUGUUCUGGAUUAUACAUUAAGAACAAGCAUUAUUUUAAUUAUGUAGUAACAUUUACUAUGACUUUGAAGCCAGAUUUCAAAAUCUGGCUUUGUUAAAUUAAUUGGAAACACUCUUCUAUUAAGUUAGGUAUUAAAAAAAGCCAAAUAUCAAUAAAGAUAUUUUUAUUAAUUUUUUAUAGAAACAAAAUAGCUACUAUAACUCUAUUAUAGUAUAUUAACAGCACUUAGUAUUAUAUUGACUUAAACAUAGUAGCUAAUAAAACUAGUUUAUGACAUCUAUUGAAAUUCUCAGUCUGACAGUUUUAAAAUAGCUUAAAACUAAGCACCAGGUAUAUGAAAAAGGAACUGGAAAUUUUAAUUGUCCAGAAAUCAUAGGAAUACUGGGAACCUGUAGUUAUGGGAAAUGGCUGUUUUUCUGAAGUUGAAACCAGUUUCAAUUACAAAACCCUCUGAAAUUUUGCUAAGCCUAUAGUUAUCUCCCUAAGAACCAUAAAAAAAGAUAAUUUUAUUGUUAAUUUCAUUCCAGUUUAGCUUCCUCAUUUUACAUGUUGGGAGUCAUGCCCUUUAAUAUGCCUGGCACUGCACGGUGGCAGUAGCAGACUUGGGCUUACCCAGAACCCUAAGUCUCUGACGCUAUAGGAUAGCGAAAGAGGUAGGCAAUCGUAACAGACACUGUAUAGGAUAAAUAGGGAAGAGAAUGAGAGAACCAAAAUAAAAAUAAUUUAAGAAACAAUUGUUUUACUGUACAUGUGAAUAACAAGAAAUGGUACGGGGAAUGUGAAUAACACGAAAUGGUAUGGGGAAUGUGUGACUAGUGAAGCAUAUUUUAACUUUUUUAUUACUGGAGGAACAGAGCUAAAGGCCUAAAGAAGGCCUUACAGUAUAUAACAGUAAAUAGAAGAGUAACAUCUUUAUACAAUAAACUGUUAGAAAUGAUAAGUGUAAAGUUGUGCGUCUCUGCGGCUCCUGAACUUGAAGAUUAUUAUGAAUAGAUUGGACCAGCAUUAUAUAUUAAAAACUUUGAUACUUAGAACUUUCCAACUUUAAAAUUCAGAAUCAUAAAUGGUGACAACAGUAGUAGUAUUGAACCAAAAAUAGUCAAGUAAAUAAUGUCUCAGUAAAGCAAAAGCAUUAUCUUCUCAAAUACAAAAAAUACAAAAUUCAUUUCUUUUCUUGACCUUGAAAAUUUCUGUUUUCCAAAUACCUAGGAAAAAUGAAUACCUUCUGCGUUGAAUCCAUGUAGCAAUCUGAAAAAAGAAAUCAAAAUGGAAUGGUACUGAAAAGCUAAUUUGUAGCACAUAACGGUAUAUAGUUCUAUACCAUUAAUACUAAAACAUGAAUACAGCAUGCUUACAGAGCCCACCCACUCCUAAUACUAGUUAUUAAAGAAACGUUACUGGCUGGGCGCAGUGGCUUAUGCCUGUAAUCCCAGCACUUUGGGAGGCUGAGGCGGGUGGAUUACCUGAGGUCAGUAGUUCGAGAACAGUCUGGCCAACAUGGUGAAACCCCGUCUCUACUAAAAAUACAAAAAUUAGCCUGGCAUGGUGGCACAUGCCUGUAAUCCCAGCUACUCGGGUGGUUGAGGCAGGAGAUUUGCCUGAACCCAGGAGGCGGAGGUUGCAGUGAGCUGAGAUUGUGCCACUGGAGUCCAGCCUGGGUGACAGAGCAAGACUCUGUCUCAAAAAAAAAAAAAAAAGAAAUGUUAUUGUCUGACUAAAUUUAUAAGAUAUGUAUUGGUUAAAACCAUGCCAUGUUGGUGCCUCUUUCAUUAGAGCCUUUAUGUCGUAAUGAAUUUGACUAAAAUUAUCUUAGACUUUCAUUAUCCCAGGCCUAAGAACUCACUGGCAUUUGUUUCAAGGUAACUGAACAAGAAGCUGUUUGGAAUUGGCAGAAGUCAGAUGAAAAACCAAUCUUACAUGCCCCUUCUUCCUCUCUUGAGCUGUUGUUUAUAUUCAAAUUAAAUACACAUUGUUUCUCUCUGUAGAUACCUAUGUACUUAAUAGAUUCUAGUUAGUAAACUGCACAUGCCCAAUAACUUUGAGGAAAUUUAGUGAAAAUGAAGAAAAAGAGAAAAUAUUUCUCUUUAGACCUGAGGUUAUGUUUAGGCUGGCCCAUAGAAACAGGUCCAGAUAAAUUUCUAAAAAAGCAAAGUAGAUAUUUAUGAAUAGUAUUCAAUGCCUAGGAUUAACAUCUAAAAUGACUCAGUAGUACUGCUAGCCAGCCAAUAAAAUAUAAACUCCAUUUGUCUUAGUUAUAUAGAACUGUGUUUCCAGCUUAGAAAAAGUCAAACCAAUGACUUUUAGAACAAUCUACUCUCAUUUUUUAUUCAGCCUCUAGAACAUGGAAGCUUUAAAAGUGAAUUGGCUAAAUAGGCAAGACCUUCUGAAAGUUAACAUCUUAAUGAUUAAAAACAGUAAGUACAGGUUAGUAAUUACCUGGGUAAUUAAUUGAAGCCUUAUUCUGUUUUCAUAAGACUUACUUGCUUAAUUCAAGCAAAACAAAUUUUGGUCUAAAUUACCUAGAUAAUUAUGACAGCUUUUUACUUGAGAAGUGUAGAACUUGCUUCAGGCUACAAAACUGUAUUAUUCCUAAAUGGAUAACCAGGUAGGAUUCUAACUGGCAUUAUUGUAUGCUUAAGAUUGAUUUAACAACAGCUAUUCCCAGUAAGGAAAUUUUAAAAAUCAGAUCCAGUUACAUGUAUUAUGAUUUUUCUACCUUAUGGACUAUUUUGGAGGGAUAAGCUAUUAAGACUAAGACUAUGAAUGAGAGUUGGGGAAGGAGCAGGAAGGGAGGAACCUGCACACCACAUUGGAACCUGCACACCACAUUAACACAAAGGCAAUCUUCUGGCUCGGACUGUUCUUUACUACUGUUCUUAAAGAAAAUGUUCAUUCUGCUGCAGCUAACUAGCCUCCAUCUUCUACACCAAAUACUAUUCCAUGCCAUGGAAGUGCUAUGCAAUAACUCUCCCAGGUAGCACCUUAUACCGCUUAAAAGCCUUUAAAAUCUCCAAUCUGAAGGUGUCACAGUAAAGAAAUGUAAACACUUAGGAAAACAAAAAUGUAAUUACCUGAUGAAGUCAUCUAUGUCCAUGGAACGGGCCCGUUUGUCACUAAAACCUGUGCUGGUUAGGAUUUGCUGUAUUUUAUCUGCUAUGCUGAAAUCUUCUGGUAUUAUCUAUCAAUAUAAGAUUCAGAAUAAAUGAACGACAUAUCUUUAA